CGCUGGCGGGCAUGCUGCGCGGGAGCCAGGCUCCGGGGCCCCGCGCCGCGCCCCUUUAUGCCCGCGCCCCGCCGCGCCCGCCCGCCCACCGCCGGCGCGCCCACCCCCGCUCCCCGGCGGGCUCCGCUGGCAAUAAUUACCUGCGAGCCGGGACUGCCUCCGCCCUGGCACUGGGGGCGGGGGCAGGGGCGCCGAGGGCGAGGGGUGCCCGGGAGGGGCGCGGCAGCGGGCAAGGUGCGGCAGGCGUCGCCCGCGGACGUCGGAGAAAGGCACCUGUUUCUCCCAGCUCCCGGGAGCCGUGCAGGACGUUUCGUGGACGCUCAGGUUCAUUCUCUUUGCCUGCCGCGCGUCCUCUGAGAGCAGCCCUGGAGCGGCUUCGUCGGGGAGAAAAGGCGCCGACCAACUUUCCCCGACUUGGGGGCGGGAUCCUGCCGGGCCCUAGCGGAGCGCGCCGCUGGGGAAGCACCUGCUCUCACUUUUCUCCCACUCGGAGGCCCAAAGAAGCUCCGGCUGGACAUUGCUGGAGCCAAUUAGGGACUGGCCGAAAUCCUAGAGGGACUGCCAGGUGGGACAGCCGAGGGGGAACUUCGCCGUGCGCUGAAAGGGAUUCCCCCUUAGGACGAUGGGAGCCUUUUAACACCAAUGGAGCAGGAGAUGCACUGAUUCACAUGCACCCAAAUACAACACCAACCCCACAAGCUCUCAGCUCACCAGUCACAGACAUCACCUUCUACGGACAUAUUUUUAUUUCACUGAGCUACAACUACGGGCAAGGCAACGACGAGCUGUGUGGAGACUUCAAAACAUAGAGGACAACCUCUGCCCUCAAAGACAACAUCCAACUGAAGAAAGGAUCAAGAAAGAUGAAAAUAAAUAAGUUGUUUGAUUAUGCUGUGUUAAUAAAUGACCCAUAGAAUAAUUGUCAGAGAAAUUCAGAAGAAGAAGAAAUUACCCUAUUUUGAGUUGUUUGGAAAAGUUUAACAGAGAAAAAUAUGACAAUAUCUGGGGUUUAAAGAGUAAAACUCGCACAAAGACCUGGAGGGAAGGAAUCAAGAGAUGCCAACACUGAAGAAAAAAACAUGUUCAUAGUGUAUUCGUGGUGAAAAGAAAGGGUUUUUGUGCGCAAGGAAGUAAUGGACCAAAAUGCAGUAGUCCCAGUGCCUAGAAUCAUGCUGAGCACAAAACAAGUAUUUGUUUAAUGAGCAAAUGAAAGUAGAGUUUCAUUUGUCCAGUUAACAAAAUACACAAGUAUUCCCUGCCCUCCUCUUUUUAAAAUUAAUUAAUUAAUUAAUUUUUAACAGACAAAAAAUUAUAUAUAUUUUCAUGUACAGCAUGUUAUUUUAAAAUAUAUACACAUUUGUAGAGUGGCUAAAUUGAGCUAAUAAACGUAUGUAUUACCUCA